GCGGCGCAGAGGCGGGCGCCUACCAGCCGGCAGCUCCGGAGCUGCCCGCGCCAUGUCCGCGCACAAUCGGGGCACCGAGCUCGGUAAGGGGCCCGCGGGGCUCCCCAUCCCCUCUCCCUCGCGUUCAGCGCCGCCGGGACUAGCGCGGGGCCUGCUGCCGCCCAGUGCCCUGGCUGUGGGUCCCCGAGGGGUUUUCGCUGGGGCGGGAAGCAGUGGCGUCUGGUCAGCCCUCACCCCAAGUAAAGGCCGAACCCGGCACGUUCGCGCCGCUUGUCUUUGCACCUAAGCUUUUACUCUUGUAUGCGGAAGGAGUAGGAAAGGGUUAGAUUAUUAUCUUCCUGCCUUUUCGUUCACUCUAGCUCGCUGGUUGGAAAACCCAACAACCCAAAAAACAAAACCCAAAACAAACAACCCCCAAGCAGGUAAAAACAGAUAAAAACCUUCUUUCUCCUCCUUUUAAUAGAAUACUUGUGUAAUUUAAUGCAGUAUUUCCGUAGAUAAUUUUAACCGUAACCUUGAAGUGGCCGUGCUCGUGGAAAAGUUGUCAGCCGUCUGUGCUCAAAAUGUAACACUGCAGAUUCAUGGGAUUUUAGAGUUACAAAGAUUUGUUAAAGUACCUGUAUUAUUUCCCAGUUUUCAUCUUUUUUUAUAUUGUUCAAAUACUGGCAAGAAACCUUAGUUCAGAUUUCUUUUUUUUUUUUUUUUAUUGAUCAUUCUUGGGUGUUUCUCGCAGAGGGGGAUUUGGCAGGGUCAUAGGACAGUAGUGGAGGGAAGGUCAGCUGAUAAACAAGUGAACAAAGGUCUCUGGUUUUCCUAGGCAGAGGACCCUGCGGCCUUCCGCAGUGUUUGUGUCCCUGGGUACUUAAGAUUAGGGAGUGGUGAUGACUCUUAACGAGCAUGCUGCCUUCAAGCAUCUGUUUAACAAAGCACAUCUUGCACCGCCCUUAAUCCAUUUAACCCUGAGUGGACACAGCACAUGUUUCAGAGAGCACAGGGUUGGGGAUAAGGUCACAGAUCAACAGGAUCCCAAGGCAGAAGAGAAUUUUUCUUCAGAUUUCUUAACAUGUGAAAAAUUUAUAAUUCAAACAGCAAAACCAUGAUCAAGAGAAGGUUUAAGCGUCUCGUUUAAGUAUUAUAGCUUGGAUAUCUGUGUAUCCAGGAUCUUUAACUUCUUACCUGUGUGACUUCGGACAAAUUAAUAACUUUGCGCUUAAGUUUCUUCAUCUGUAAAAUGGUUAUUUUAGUGGUAGUUACCUUAUAAGGCCGUUAGGAGAUUAAAUAGGAUACAUGUAAAGUAGUUUGGUAUAUUGUGGACACCUAGUAAGUCUUCAGUAUAGAUAGUAUUAGUAUAUGGAGUUAUGGUUUUAGGGGCUAAUUUUGAGAAAAUUGGCUGUAAAUUAUAUGUAACACAUACAGGUAGGUCCUUUUCGCCCUCCUUAAAAGUGACUGGUACUUAAACAGUCUGCACUUCCAAGAGGUGUUCUGGAUUUUUUGUCGAAUGGUAAGAGAGUAAAUCUAUCAUUUUAAAGACAGUUGAUUUACUAACCUGGUUGAUUUUGUUUUAGUCACUGUCCUCUAGCUGAUUAUGUUUUAAACUCUAGUCCUAUCUCUGGAACGUGGUCUUUAGUAAUAACGGCAUUAUUUCUUAGAUUGGAAUAUCCUUGAAGGUGGUGGAUAUGGGGCAGGUUUGGGGUGGUGUCUUACCUGGGUAUUCCCAGGAAUAUGACCAUGUGACUAUGCAUACAUCAAGGAUGUGCCCUAAAUUUCCCAAAACUUAGACAUUUUAAAUUUUUCUUUCAAAAAACAUAAUUGAACCAUUUUUAAAUUUAUUUAUUUGCAGUAAUUAGAAUCAAUCACUUCCAUUCAUUUGUUGAAAAGUAAUAGACAUAAAUAAUUGCCAGGUAGAACAAUAGUAAAUGUGGUUUUUAUGCAGCUAUCGAAAUGAUCAUAGCUUUGUAUUUAUUAUCUUAUUUGUUAAAAUCAGAUUUUUUUCCUUCACGGGUAUUAAUCCUUAAUCCAAACAGGUUUAAACUGAAAUGCUAAAAUAAGUUAUUUGAAUUAGGUACUAGGGAAAAAAAUCUUUCAGUAUUAAUUUAUGCAGUAUAUUAACUGAUGAUUUUUAAAAUAGUUUUCUAAUUGAAAGUCUUUUUAAUAAACAUCGUAACUAAUUUCUAAAAUAAAUUAACAUUUUUGCUUCCCUUUUCUUAUUACAAAAGGAAUUCAUGGUUAUUGUAAAAAUUCUAGAAAAUACAGUUAGCACAAAAAUGUUGUAAUAUUAUUACUAGUCCAAUCACUGUUAUUUAUGAUUUGGUGUAUGUACUUCUAGUUCAUGGACUUAAAAAAACAUUGAGUUCCUUUGAGACUAAACCUGACCCUCAUGAUUAAAAAGUCUUUAAGGAAAACAUUGGCAUUUGGAUGUAUGAAAGAUGUUUUCCAAAUAGGGAAUGUACCCUCUAGCUUUCAUAUUAGAGGAUGGGGCCCAGCAUUCUGAGUUUUAACAAAUCCUGUGGGUAGUACUGAAGCAUACCCAAGUUUGAGAACCAAUGGCUUAAUGAUCUCCAAGGUACUAUCAAGUUUUGUACCUAGACUAUUAUGCCCUAUAUAGUCUAUUAAAAUGUACAGAUAUUCUUCUAUUUUAUUAGAUGCCACUUAACUAUUGCCUAAAAUGCAGGUGUCACGUGGGUAGUGAUCUUUCUUUUGUUCACUGAUGUGUCCCAAGUACCUAGAAUAGUGUUUGGUACACAGAAGGCCCUCAAAAAUGUCUUGAGGCUGGGCAUGGUGGCUCAUGCCUAUAGUCCUGGCACUUUGGGAGGCUCAAGGCAGCCGGAUCACUUGAGAUCAGAAGUUGGAGACCAGCCUGGCCAACAUGGCAAAACCCUAUCUCUACUAAAAAUACAAAAAUUAGCUGGGCAUAGUGGCGCAUGCCUGUAGUCCCAGCUACUUGGGAAGCUGAGGUACGAGAAUCGCUUGAACCCAGAGAGUGGAGGUUGCAGUGAGCUGGAAUUGUGCCACUGCACUCCAUUGGGCAACAGACUGGAGACAGACUGUGUCUCAAAAAAGAUAAAAAAAAAAAAAAAAAAAGAAAAAGUCUGUUGAAUGAAGGAAUGAAUUGAGAGCUGCUUCUUACUUGGGGGAACUGGGGAAUCUACCUGGUCCCCGUGUAUGGUUGCAUGGACAGAUGCUGUGAAGCUUGGCACCUUCUUCCUCUUUGUAAGUAUUAUUAAGAUUCAGUUUUGUUACAUCCGUCUUCAGAGCUAUCUCAAGAAGCCUAUAAAGGAUGUAGAUAGUGUAACUUCCUUGCAAAUGUUAUCUUUGGAGGCGUCUGGAGAAUGCGGGUGUUAUUAGAUGACUUCUAAGGAUCUCCCUGCUCUGUCUCUGUGUGUCUGAAAACUCUUCUGUUCAAAAAGCAACAUUUCAAAGAUAUCUGAAAAAUAACCAUGAUGGGAUUUUGUAUUUUUUUUCGAGACAGAGUCUCCCUCUGUUGCCCAGGCUGGAGUGCGGUGGUGUGAUCUUGGCUCACUGCAACCUCCGUCUCCCAGGUUCAAGCAAUCCUCCUGCCUCAGCCUCCCGAGUAGCUGAGAUUACAGGUGCCUGCCACCAAGCCCGGCUAAUAUUUUUAUAUUUUUAGUAGAGACGGGUUUUUGCCAUGUUGGCCAGGUUGGUGGGAUUUUUUUAUUUUAAGAAGCACAUUUAUUUAGGUAGUUAUUGAGUACCAAUCUGUACUGGGUAGUAUUACCCUAGGCUGGGGGUACAAGAUAAUCAGGGAUGGUCACUGCCUUCACAGAGCUAUUAAUCGGUCUGGUUCAGGACCUGGACAUCAAGCUAGAGCUACAAUUAAAUGCAAGUGUGAUGUGCAAUUAUUUUUCAUUUAUUUUUGUCUAAAAUUAGAUAGAUGUACCUAGACUGUGCUUUAAAUGGGUUGUGAAAACAGAAUGUCCUGGGCCUUUUGCAUUAUAAUUUUUAAUUUCCUUUUAAAAGAACCUAUGAAUUAGGGAUUUAGGGAGCUCAUUUUUGGCAUUCCUGCUAAAGUAUAACUUGGGUACAGAAUGUUUCUGAUUUGGGUGAUGGUGAUUUUCCACUGCAAAGUUAACGUUUAAUUUUUGGAAUGGAUAUUUAUUUAUUUAUUUGUUUAUUUAUUGUUUCAAUAGAGACCGUGUGUCAGUAUGUUGACCAGACUGUUCUCAAACUCCUAGCCUCAAGUGAUACUCCAGCCUCUGCCUCCCAAAGUGCUAGGAUUAUAGGCAUGAGCCACCGUGCAUGGCCUAGAAUGGCAUCUUAAACCUCAACAAUAGGCAAAGGCUAUCUGUUUGCAUAAUAAUUCUUCACCUUAUUUAAUACCUACUGUGUGCAGACACUGUGCUUAGGUGCUGGGUAUAAUGAUAGUGUCAACACAGAGCUCUAGCUACUUGUAAGGCACUAUGCUGAAUGCUUGAAAUUCUCAUUUAGUCCACAAUGGCCCUGUGAGGGAGAUAGCAUGAUCCAGGUUUACACACGAGCAAACUGAGGUACAGGGAGUUUUAAGUAACCUGCCGAAAACCAGUUAGGUAUAGCUAAUGUGGCAGAGCCAGAAUUCAAGCCCAGGUGAUUUGGUGCUAAUAAUGCUACAUGCUUAAACAACCACACUGUGUCGACUGGUGCUAACUGGGAGCACUACACCCUGAUGUCAGAAGAGUCAAAUAGAUAACUGGUGAAUACUGUUAAUGUUACUCUUUUAGGUUUGAUUUGUCUGUUUAAAACAUAAAGGUUACUGUUUUAUUGCCAUAACCCACAUCUUAACCAUUGCAGUUUGUUUCAGAGAAGAUGCAAUUUAUCCUGAGGGAGAAUGGAAAAGUCCAAACUUUGGUAGAUUAUGAGAGUAGGGUUCGAUGUUAGUGAAGUUUUCAAGGAUGGCAUGUCAAAACCAGACUUCCUCAGGAACUGCUUCAUGUGGAUAUACUGAUGAGCCUCAGAGCAUCAUGUGAUGGUGACCAGGGAGUGACCUCAAGACCUUAGCUGGAUCUCCAAAAUACAAGUGAAUCACCCGGCAGUUCUGAGGCGUGCGGAACAAAUCCAGGCUCGCAGAACCGUGAAAAAGGAGUGGCAGGCUGCUUGGCUCCUGAAAGCUGUUACCUUUAUAGAUCUUACUACACUUUCAGGUGAUGAUACAUCUUCCAACAUUCAAAGGCUCUGUUAUAAAGCCAAAUACCCAAUCCGGGAAGAUCUCUUAAAAGCUUUAAAUAUGCAUGAUAAAGGCAUUACUACAGCCGCCGUUUGUGUUUAUCCCGCCCGGGUGUGUGAUGCUGUAAAAGCACUCAAGGCUGCAGGCUGUAAUAUCCCUGUGGCAUCAGUGGCCGCUGGAUUUCCAGCUGGACAGACUCAUUUGAAGACACGAUUAGAAGAGAUCAGAUUGGCUGUGGAAGAUGGAGCUACAGAAAUCGACGUGGUAAUUAACAGAAGCUUGGUGCUGACAGGCCAGUGGGAAGCCCUGUAUGAUGAGAUUCGUCAGUUUCGCAAGGCCUGUGGGGAGGCUCAUCUUAAAACUAUAUUAGCGACAGGAGAACUUGGAACUCUUACUAAUGUCUAUAAAGCCAGUAUGAUAGCAAUGAUGGCAGGAUCAGAUUUUAUUAAGACCUCUACUGGAAAAGAAACAGUAAAUGCCACCUUCCCGGUAGCUAUAGUAAUGCUGCGGGCCAUUAGAGAUUUCUUCUGGAAAACUGGAAACAAGAUAGGGUUUAAACCAGCAGGAGGCAUCCGCAGUGCAAAGGAUUCCCUUGCUUGGCUCUCUCUUGUAAAGGAGGAGCUUGGAGAUGAGUGGCUGAAGCCAGAACUCUUUCGAAUAGGUGCCAGUACUCUGCUCUCGGACAUUGAGAGGCAGAUUUACCAUCAUGUGACUGGAAGAUAUGCAGCUUAUCAUGAUCUUCCAAUGUCUUAAAUCAGUCACCAGUUCCAGAAAAGUUCUUUACGACAAUGUUUAAAAAUUAUUUUUCUACGUAAUUGCUAAAAUUAUUUAAUUAAAAAAUUGGGCAGUAGGUAACUGGCAUUCCUCUCUUUAAAAUUUCUACCGAACUUAAUGGAAUGGAAAAAGCAAACUCAUCCACAUGUGGUACUCAUUUCAGGCACAUCUGAAAUGAUCUUAAUUACUAGAAGAUCUGCACUAUUAACUUUGUGAAGAGUUUCUCCUAAAAACUUUAAGUAAAAUGUUAAUGGUAGCUUUGAUAACAUCAAAUUCUAAGGGAGAAAAAAACAAUAUUAAACCGCCCAAGCAGUGUGCCCUAGCAGAGGAAAAUGCAACAUCUCGCAAGCGCUGCUGUAACGACUUCAGGAGUCACUGAUUCAGCACUAAUUUCCUGCUGUGAAAACUCAUCUUUCAUUUUUGCCGUGGAUAGGCGCUUUUAUUAAUUGUUGUCCUAAUGAAAUUUCUGACAUUGUCAUAUACAACGAUGAAUAUCAUUAAAAUUUUUAAAAUAAUAAAGUUCCUAUAGUUUAUUUUUUUAAAAAACUUAAAAAUUGUUACAAUACAUAAUGAAAAAAUAAUCCAUUAAACAUAAAAAGAGGUUUGAUCAGUGA